AUUGGCCUUAUCCCAGUGAUUCUCUGAUUUGUUUGGUCUGGGGUGGGACUUAACUAUCAAUAUUAAUCUUCCCUAGUGAGGCUAAUGUGCAGCCGUGAUGGAGAACCACUGAACCAUAAGCAAUUUUUGCUUAUUGAAUGUUAGUUGAGGAAAUCUGUGCUUUACUUAAUUCUUUUUUUUUUUUUUUUUUCUGAGACAGAGUCUUGUUCUGUCACCCAGGCUAGAGUGCAGUGGCGCAAUCUCGGCUCACUGCAACCUCUGCCUCCCGGGUUCACGCCAUUCUCCUGCCUCAGCCUCCCGAGUAGCUGGGACUACAGGCACCCGCCACCAUGCCCGGCUGAUUUUUUAUAUUUUUAGUAGAGACGGGGUUUCACCGUGUUAGCCAAGAUGGUCUCGAUCUCCUGACCUUGUGAUCCGCCCGCCUCGGCCUCCCAAAGUACUGGGAUUACAGGCAUGAGCCACCGCGCCCGGCAUACUUAAUUCUUUAAAAUUAUUUUCUGCUUUGAAGGACCUGUUUAUUUUUGUAGAGAUUAACGUCCUAAUUAUGUUUCAUUAUAUUAAAAAUGUUUUGCAUUUUCCAAUUAAAACAAAAUCAGCACAUGAGUAAUCAAAGGAUUACUUGUAUAUUAAGAUAAUCACUUGGUUUCCUAAUGCUAGAAAAUACAUUUCCUUCAUCUUAGAUGGAUGACAUUUUAUAUGCUUUAUUCUUUAAAGGUCUUUCAAUCCUGAUGGAAAACUGGCAUUUAACCAGUUGAGAAAAGAUCACAUCAUAUUAAGUAAAGGCUUAGCAAAAUGUUUUUUAGAAAUACUCUGAAAGCAUUCUUAUAUUUCCUAUGCUAGAGAAAAUGACUCAACACAUUUAUUCUGUAUUAUUUCAGUCAUGAAAAAUGUUACAAUAUUCAGUUGGUGCAAAUAAAAAAUAAAAGCAAUUUAAGUAAUUACACUCUAUCCAAAUUAUUGAUUUCAUGUUUGGCGGAAAAACCUGGAGAAUGGAAUAGUUAAUUGAACUUUACUUUGUUGUAAACCAGUUUUUUAAGGUAUUUGUAUUCUCUAUCUCUUCUCCUUUUGCCUUCCUCAGCCUUUCCCAAAAAAGACUGUAAUUACGUUAUUUGUAACAAAUAACUGGCAGAAUAAUUGCCAGAAUAACUAGUGGGUGAUUAGCAGUUUUAAAGUUAAACCAUUAACAGAGGAACAGUAGUGAAGUGUGGUGUAAAUCAACUUGUAACUAAAUUCUUGUUUUUUUGUUUGUUUGUUUUUUUGAGACAGAGUUUCAUUCUUGUUGCCCAGGCUGGAGUGCAAUGGUGGGAUCUCUGCUCACCGCAACCUCCGCCUCCCGGGUUCAAGUGAUUCUCCUGCUUCGGCCUCCCAAGUACCUGGGAUUAACAGGCAUGCGCCACCAUGCCUGGCUAAUUUUGUAUUUUUAGUAGAGACGGGGUUUCUCCAUGUUGGUCAGGCUGGUCCCGCACUUCUGACCUCAGGUGAUCCGCCCGCCUUGGCUUCCCAAAGUGCUGGGAUUACAGGCGUGAACCACUGUGCGCGGUCUAUCCUGAAGAUCUUUACCUAAUGUUUAUCCAAUAUAGCUAGCCAUUUCUAGUUCAACCACAAAGCAAAAAUGCUUCCAGGAAGCAUUUAUUCACAGAAAAGACUCAGAUCUCAUUUACUCCUAAUUCAGAUAGUUCUAACAGGAGGUGGGGUCUCCUAGCCUAUGGCAAUUGAUUAGAAACAAAUUUUGUAAAAAGUUAAGUAGCCUGUUACAGAAAGGAAGACUGAAAGUUCCAAGAAGUGAGAGCUUUUAGUGUAAAGCUGUUAGUUGUAGAGGGAAAGCCAACUUACAAGAGCAGACAAUUUUCAGAGUUGUUUUAGAAUUCUUGUGUUUAGUUCAGUUUACGCCAAGAAUAUUCAAGAUCAUAAGCACGUUAAAUCACAAUAUGGUAAUUGAUUAUAAUGGUAACCCUGAGGUUUUUUUUUUUUUUUUUUUUUUUUUGAGAUAGUUUCACUCUUGUUGCUCAGGCUGGUGUGCAGUGGCACCAUCUUGGCUCAUGGCAACUUCCGCCUCCUGUUCAAGCGAUUCUCCUAUCUCAGCCUCUGAGUAGCUGGGAUUACAGCCACACGCCACCACACCUGGCUAAUUUUUUAUAUUUUUAGUAGAAAUGGGGUUUCACCAUGUUGGCAAGGCUGGUCUUGAACUCCUGACCUCAGGUGAUCCACACGCCUCGGUCUCCCAAAGUGCUGUGAUUACAGGCAUGAGCCACUGUGCCCGGCCGAGUAUUAUUUUUAAAACUAAAUUAUGCUAGGUACACUCUUAACAAGGCAAGGAUUUCCAUUCACAAAAGGAAGCGUAAAUUAUGCAGGCUAAAUGAAGCACUGUCAUACCCAAAAUAUUAGAUACAAUAUUUUCUUAUGAUUUAACUUUUACAAAGGGCCUCUUUGUCAGAAGUUGCUGAAGUUCCCGGUUCAGCCUAUUAUUGCUGCAUAUUCUUGAAAACAAAAUUGUUGAUGAUUCAGAUGUAUGUGUGACUGUGCGAAGAAAACCCCUCCAUUUCUGUUGCUGUAGGACUUUGUUGCAAUUAGCUUGCUGAACUUGAUUUUCUCUUUGAACUGUUGUGAUUGCUUUGUACAUCCUAUAAAUAAUUUACCCCUGAUGGUACUAAACGACUACAUUAAUGGCACCUCUGGCUCCACAUGAUAUCAAGGACAUUAAUAAUUCAUCAUUUAUUACAGCUACAUCCUUGUAGAUUAGCAUGAGUGGGAACUGAGUUUACAACAUUGAGAUCAGGCCCUCUGAGAGACCUUUACUCCUCUGUCAUCAUAUCUAUAAAUAUUCAGAUAUUAGUGGUGUUAGAAAAUAAAGGAAGGACUGUUACAGAGCUAGACUUUAGGUUUAAGUUUAUUAAGCAUUAGGUUUACAGCCUGGGCAACAUAGGGAGACCCCAUUUCUACAAAACAGAAUAAAUUAGCUGGGCUUGGUGGCAUUUGCCUGUGGUCCCAGCUGUAAGGAGACUGAGGUAGGAGCAUUGCUUGAGCCUGGGAGGUGAAGGCUGUAGUGAGGUGUGAUGUCACCACUGCAUUUCAGCCUAGGCAACAGAGCUUUAGAUUACUUCAAGUUCUUAAGUACAUUUUAGGGAUAUUUGAAAGAGAGUUCUCCAUUUCAGGACUCCUGCUUUUUAAAAAAAAAUUAUGCAAACCACCUGGAAUUAAUGGACAUUGGGAAGAACAGUGAGAGACUUCAAUUUUUAAAAUCAUCCAAAUCCAUAUUCCAAGAGUUUUAAAUCUGAUAUUUGAAGUCUUCAUUUAUUUGUUUAUUUUUAAUUUUUUAAUUUUUUGGGGGAUGGAGUCUAGCUCAGUCAUCCAGGCUGGAGUGCAGUGGCACGAUCGCAGCUCACUGCAACCUCCACCUCCUGGGUUCAAGCGAUUCUCCUGCCUCAGCCUCCCGAGUACCUGGGAUUACAGGUGCUUGCCACCAUGCCUGGCUAAUUUUUGUAUUUUUUGUAGAGACGGGGUUUCACCAUGCUGGCCAGGCUUGUCUCGAACUCCUGACCUCAGGCGAUCCACCCACCUCGGCCUCCCAAAGUGCUGGGAUUACAGGUGUGAGCCACUGCGCCUGGCCCCGAAGUCUUCAUAUUUUAGUCUUCUGUCUUUUGGGAGGUACUUUUAAAAAAAGAAAUAGGAAAGGCAUGCUUACGGGGAACACGAGUAUGCCUGUGCACUCCUGUGUGCACGUGUCAUUUGAUCAAAUUCCAGAGUGAAAUUAGGCGUAAAAGCUAAUUUACCCAUUUGCAGUAAAGGAGAAUAGUAGAGUUGAUGUUGAAUUUUCUUACAGUUUUGGAGUGACUGCACCUCUGAGAAUUGUUAAGUGUUGCUUUUGGAAAAAGAAAAAGGUUACUAAAGUUGACAGUGCUUACAACCCUAGCGCUUAGUCCACUGCCUGGCACAUGGUCCAAUAAGUGUUUAUUGUAUGCAUGACUGAUCAGAUCAAUCCAUGUAAUUCUAGUUAGACACUUGAUAACUUAAAACAGUUGUACUGAUGCUGAUGUAUAUUAGUUGCUUUCUAUGAUAGUACUGCUUUGGGAAUAUAUUUCAGUUCACCUUUAGUGUUUUUUAAUCUUAAUAAAUGUGGGUUUGUUUUAGAGGGUCCAGAGAGCCUCAUUAUAUGGGGCUCUGACCUAUAAUGGCUGUUUGAAAGCAUAUAUCCUUUCAACAACAUUUUCCGGUACAGAGGCUGCAAAGCAUUUCAGGUAUCCUUUGGGUUGCAUUGAAAAGCCUAUAGGUUCUUCAAAGAUAGGAGAAAAUUACUCUUUCCCAAAACAGAGGACACUGGACAGUUUUCACUAAUACCAAAUACUAAGUUAUUUAUAACGUAUAAAUUGAGUUUCAUUUUAUUGCUUUAGAUUUCUUUAAUAAUUAUUUUCUUUAAAAAUGAUUAUGUGGGUCAAUGAUUAUUGACAAUCAUAGGAGAACUCUAGGGGAUGAAUACAGUCAAGAGUUACAUUGCCAGGAAGAUUUAGGGUUGGGAAAGGCAUUAUGAACACUGUUAGGAUUAAAAUGAAAGCCCUUAAUCUGGAAGGGGAAAACUGCUAAGUUAUAGUAGUCACCAGAUACAAAAUUAGAUCAUAUUAUGCUAGCCUGCUACACAGAUGAUAUUAGCUCUUCAUUUGCCAGACUAACCAGCUUGGAGUAGAAUAUAGAAUAUCUAACUUAAAUUAAAACAGUUGAAUUUCUCCUUGAGUCAAAACACCACAAAACAACAACAAAAAACAUCUUUUCACUUAUAUUUUUAUACGAGUGUAUGUGUUUAUUGUUUAGUAGCAAGAGUGAAUUGGAUGAAGUAUCUGAAUAUGAGAUUUUUAUGUGUAGUGAAUUCAUAUUUUUAUCUUUUAUAUUUUCUGACACCCUCCUCCAUUCAUGAGUGUCCUUGAGCUGAUACCUUGUGCCAGACAUCUUGGAAUAUUUUAGAACUGUUGUGGAAAAGUGAUGGUUUAACACACAGCUUUAGUUAUGUCAUGGUGUAAAUUAAGCUCUUAAAUGAAAGUGGCUAGCUUUUACUGAUAGGCCGGCAUGAAUCUAGCUGAGAACAAAUUGUUCUAAUGUGAUAGAGACAUUAUUCAAACCUGCAUGCAUCUGUCAACUGCCUAUGGUGGCAUAGUGAGAUAAAGUGAUCUGUAAUGUUUCUGUAAUGUGUCCCUGUUGCUAGCCAUAUUGUAACAUACAGCACAUCUUUUAGGCAGACAGCUUGUGUGGGCUGCAUUCCACCUCAGCCUUGUAAAGAUGCCAGAAGCAUCAAGGGAUUUCAGUCAUAAUCGGUUGUCUAACUGGAACAUCAGCUUGGAAUCACAAACAUUACAGGAAGUGAAAAUGAAUUACAAUGAACUAACAGAAAUCCCGUAUUUUGGAGAACCUACAUCUAAUAUUACUCUACUUUCAUUAGUCCAUAAUAUAAUCCCAGAAAUAAAUGCACAGGCACUCCAGUUUUACCCUGCUCUGGAGAGUUUAGACCUCAGCUCAAAUAUAAUAUCAGAAAUCAAGACAUCUUCAUUUCCUCGCAUGCAGCUUAAAUACCUGAAUUUAAGUAAUAACAGAAUAACCACCUUGGAGGCUGGUUGCUUCGAUAAUUUAUCAAGUUCCUUAUUAGUGGUAAAGUUAAACCGUAACCGAAUGAGCAUGAUUCCACCUAAGAUCUUCAAGCUGCCUCACCUCCAAUUCUUGGAACUUAAAAGAAACAGAAUUAAAAUUGUGGAAGGUCUUACAUUCCAAGGGCUUGACUCCUUAAGAUCUUUGAAAAUGCAGCGGAAUGGAAUUAGCAAACUUAAGGAUGGAGCAUUUUUUGGCUUGAAUAACAUGGAAGAACUAGAACUGGAACACAACAACCUUACACGAGUAAACAAGGGGUGGUUGUAUGGCUUGCGAAUGUUACAGCAGCUCUAUGUGAGCCAGAAUGCUAUUGAAAGAAUCAGCCCUGAUGCAUGGGAGUUCUGCCAAAGACUAUCCGAACUUGAUUUGUCCUAUAACCAGCUGACCCGCCUGGAUGAAUCUGCCUUUGUGGGUCUGAGCUUAUUGGAGAGAUUGAAUUUAGGAGACAACAGAGUCACUCAUAUUGCUGAUGGUGUAUUUAGAUUUCUUUCCAAUCUUCAGACAUUAGACUUAAGAAACAAUGAAAUUUCAUGGGCCAUAGAAGAUGCUAGUGAAGCCUUUGCUGGACUCACAAGUCUCACUAAACUAAUCUUACAAGGAAACCAGAUUAAGUCAAUUACAAAGAAAGCAUUCAUUGGUCUUGAAUCCCUUGAGCAUCUAGAUUUGAACAAUAAUGCUAUAAUGUCUAUCCAAGAAAAUGCUUUUUCUCAGACUCAUUUAAAAGAACUGAUUCUGAACACAAGCAGUUUGCUCUGUGACUGCCAUUUGAAGUGGCUACUUCAAUGGUUGGUUGAUAAUAACUUUCAACAUUCUGUGAAUGUAAGCUGUGCACACCCUGAAUGGCUAGCAGGGCAAAGCAUCCUGAAUGUGGAUCUGAAAGAUUUUGUCUGUGAUGAUUUUCUCAAGCCACAGAUAAGGACACAUCCUGAAACCAUAAUUGCUCUAAGAGGCAUGAAUGUGACUCUGACGUGCACUGCAGUGAGCAGCAGUGAUUCACCCAUGUCCACUGUGUGGCGCAAAGACAGUGAAAUCCUGUAUGACGUGGAUACUGAGAAUUUUGUUCGUUAUUGGCAGCAAGCUGGAGAAGCUCUGGAAUAUACUAGUAUCUUACAUCUUUUCAAUGUGAAUUUCACAGAUGAAGGAAAAUAUCAGUGUAUUGUUACUAAUCACUUUGGUUCUAAUUAUUCUCAGAAAGCCAAACUGACUGUAAAUGAGAUGCCAUCUUUUCUGAAAACGCCAAUGGAUCUGACUAUUCGCACUGGUGCCAUGGCCAGAUUAGAAUGUGCUGCAGAGGGACACCCUGCACCUCAGAUUUCCUGGCAGAAAGAUGGUGGUACUGACUUUCCUGCGGCUCGAGAAAGACGCAUGCACGUCAUGCCCGAGGAUGACGUCUUCUUUAUUGCCAAUGUGAAAAUAGAAGAUAUGGGAAUCUAUAGCUGCAUGGCACAAAAUACAGCAGGAGGUCUCUCAGCAAAUGCUUCCCUAACAGUGUUAGAGACACCCUCAUUUAUUAGACCCCUGGAGGAUAAGACAGUAACACGAGGUGAAACUGCGGUGUUACAGUGCAUAGCUGGAGGGAGUCCUGCCCCUCGUCUCAACUGGACUAAAGAUGAUGGGCCUUUGCUGGUGACAGAACGACAUUUCUUUGCUGCAGCCAAUCAGCUUCUCAUCAUUGUAGAUGCCGGGCUAGAAGAUGCUGGGAAAUAUACCUGCAUUAUGUCUAACACCCUUGGGACAGAACGUGGCCACAUUUACCUAAAUGUCAUUUCAUCCCCCAAUUGUGACUCUUCCCAGAGUAGCAUUGGGCAUGAAGAUGAUGGCUGGACCACAGUUGGCAUUGUCAUCAUUGUUGUGGUCUGCUGUGUUGUUGGCACUUCUUUGAUCUGGGUCAUUGUUAUUUACCACAUGAGAAGGAAAAAUGAAGACUAUAGUAUCACAAACACAGAGGAGCUCAAUCUGCCUGCAGACAUUCCCAGCUACUUGUCUUCCCAAGGAACGCUGUCUGAGCCACAGGAAGGCUACAGCAACUCUGAGGCAGGCAGUCAUCAGCAACUUAUGCCUCCUGCCAAUGGAUAUAUACACAAAGGCACUGACGGUGGCACUGGUACCCGGGUGAUUUGCUCAGAUUGUUAUGACAAUGCCAACAUCUACUCCAGGACCCGAGAAUACUGUCCAUACACCUAUAUUGCUGAGGAGGACGUUCUUGAUCAGACACUGUCCAGCCUCAUGGUCCAAAUGCCUAAAGAGACAUAUUUAGUACAUCCUCCCCAGGAUACUACUGCCCUAGAGAGCCUGAUACCGUCAGCCAACAGAGAGCCAUCUGCCUUUCCCACCAACCAUGAGAGGAUAAGUGAGAAGAAACUUCCCUCCACACAGAUGAGCGGUGAAACAUUGCAGCGGCCCGUGUGGAACAUAAACAGAGAACUAGGCCUGCCUCAUCCUCCUUUUUCCCAGCAGCCAGUCCAUGAGUCACCACAACUUCAUCAAAAUGAGGGCCUGGCAGGGAGAGAGCCAGACUGUUCUGCUUCUUCCAUGUCCUGCCACAGGUUACAGGAUCAUGCUUUUGAUUUUAGUAGGACUCGGAACAUUCAAGAUGGUAGUGAGGGCACAUGAAACUCACUUCAGGAUGAAAUCUGGGCAGAGACUUAUUAAUUAAUUUUGCAUUUACUACCUCAGAGCUCAGAAGAAACUCCGAAGUCAGCAUUUGCUUUACUCUUUCUUUAUGAUUGCAUCUGACCGCACCAAGGUGGGCCAUGCGUUGUUUGGUCUUAUACCUGAUGAAGAAAUGGCAACAGCUGACAGAAAUGGGUACAGCUCAUCAAAAAUGUGCAGCACCGGCAGAGGGAAGAUACGGGGCAAAUGUGCUUCCUGAUGCUUCCAUGGGGAUGUGCCCUGGUGUGCAUCUGCUUGUCAGGAAGAGUCACAUUGCUGCUUAACAUGCUGGAUUGCCCUAGUCUUCAGAAUGGUCCUGAGAAAACAUCACUACUUCGAUGUUCUACUUUGCUUUCCAAGGAGCAAAAAUAACUUUGGAGCCUUCUGGGAAGUGUGCCUGGGAUUCUUCAGUGGUUUCAGGCAGAUAGUUGAGACUGGGGCUUUGAUAUUCAAGGUCUUUGGCAAGAAUCCCAGGCUUGACCAACUGGUACCAGGUCAAAGAUUUUUGUAUUCUUGUGAAUUUUUUUUUUUGUCCCUAUUGCCCAGGGAUGUCAUUGUAAAUAUAUGUGCAUUUAUAAAUAAUUUUUGUAUUCAUUGACCAUAUGUGUUGGCUGCAAUGUAAAUAUUUUUGAUAUGCCAAAAUUAUAUGUAAUAUCCAGUUAUAAUAUUGACAAGUAGCUUCUCAGAUCACAGAUUUUAAAUAACUCAAUUUAGUGAGAUCUAAAAAUUUUAUUUAAAGUAUAAAAACUGUGGCUCACACCUGUAAUCCCAGCAUUUUGAGAGGCUAAGGUGGGAGGAUUGCUUGAGGCCAGGAAUUUGAGACCAGGCUGGGCAACAUGGUGAGACCCUGUGUCUGCAAAAAAAUAAAUUAAAAAAAUAGGUGGACAUUGUGGCAUGCUGCUGUAGUCCUAGCUACUUGGGAGGCUGAGGUGGGAGGGUCACUUGAGCCCGGGAAAUCAAGGCUGCAGUGAGCUGUGUGAAGCCACUGCAUCCCAGCCUGGGUGACAGAGUGAGGCCCUGGCUCAAAAGUAAAAUAAAUAAAUAAAAAGUUUUAAAAACUUACUUGUUAAGAAGUGUAUCUAUAGAGGCAGCUACUUAGUGAUUGUAUACACAUAAACACAGUCUUGGUGUAAUUAACCGCCUUCUUCAUGCCUAGAGGUUCAUACUUCUGGUCAUUUGCCAUCUGUUUAAAAGUGCUAGGUGAUACUCCCUUUCUAACAUAAAAAGCUUGUUCUUUCAGAGCCUGGCAGUCCUGUCACAGCUGUAUGCACCUAGAGGAAAACUUGUUUGGAAAUUCCUUUCAUUUCCUCCCCCUCUCCCUCCUUCCCUCUUUUUUUUUACUGAAACAGAAAUUGAUUGAGGAAGGUUCAGUCAUUCCUUCAGGAACCAAUGAGUUAGAUCGGGUUGUUACUUUAUGUAUAAUGAACGCUUCAAAAACUGGAGGCUGAUUUAAAGAUUGCAGAACUUGAGUCAGACUCAUAAGCAGUACUGUGACAUGAAUUGGAGCCAGAACAGUUGCUGAUAUCAGAACCAUCUCUUUCAUUCUGUGACUUUGCUCUUGCCAUGUUCUGACUGGGGUGAGCCGCUAGGAUACAAAUCACUAUCACUGUCCAUAUUUGAGUCUGCAAAUCUUGUCAUUGUCUGCUUUAAUGCUCUUUGAGUUGCAACAGGUGUAUUAUUUAAAUGAGUAUUUGAAAUUCUGUGAACAGGAAUUCUUUUGGUAGUGAAAUAGGUGCUCACACCUGCUUGCUCAGAAUGUGAAAAUAUUAUUUCUGAGUUCUCUUUGUUCACUUUCUAAAGUGACUGUUGUUUGGUGUUGGAGAUGUUAACUGGGUUCUAUUAGGUGUGCUAUAUCUUGGCAAAUAUUCCCCAUGAUGAACUCUUCCUACUAUCACAAUCAGGACUAUGACUGGAUUUCUCAGUCUCAGUGCCCCAGAUUCACCAUUUCUGAUUGUGUCUGGAGAACGUUUUCCUGGAAAGGCAUUCCAUGUUCCAAAAGCUACAAAAACAUGCCACUUUGCAACUAUGGGUCAGUUAUUUGCUCUCUCAAUGUCUCAUGUUGCUGAGUUCUAGAAAAUCUCUGUCUCAUUUACCAGGGGUCAUUCAAAAGUCUGAGAUGUAUAUUAUCAUGAAAUAUUUGUGAAAUUUCUCACCAUGAAUUUGGAGGGAACCUACUUUUAUUUCUCGCUCUGGUUCUCCAUUGGUCUGGGCUCCUGCUUCUCAGUCUUCUCUGACCUCUGGUAAGUGGAACUUUCAUUAAUACUUCUGUCGCACUUUGUACCUGACCUAGGUGGCCUUGCAAAUGUUGACUCAGAUUGUGGAUUUUCCACUUUCCUCUGUUUUCCCUAUUUUCUCCCCUGGGAAAUCUUGCAGAUGAUGCAUAUUCAUUUUCUGUAUUCAGCCUUCCAUUAUUAAGGAUAAAAUUGAUCCCUACAUUGAAUCUGAAAUUACCACUAUAUGGAUUACUCUGGCUCACUGCUGUCCAAGCUUGGUUUUCUCUUUGCUUACUUCCUGUCAUAUUUUCAGUUUGCCCAAAAGAGGUAAGCCACUUUAUUACAGACCCAUUACUAGUGCUAGACGUCAUCCACCUCUGUUUUCACCUGAUUCUUGUGGGGAAUCCUCUUUAAUUUGUUGUAACCUUCUCAGCAACUCUUCUGUACUUCACCUAUAGUGCCUAGCAAAUUGUUAUCACUCAUAAGCCUGUAAUCUUCAUCACUCAGGUUAUUUGCAAGUAGAAAGCUUCUGGAACCAUUUGUCCAUCCGACUUCUGCACUGGGCCACAUCCAUCUUCUUCAUUGUCAGAAUCUGAGUUUUCUGUCUUGAAGAACAGCUGGAAAGUUGUCUGGCUGUUAUGACACAGUAUUGAAAUACCAGACUGAGUUUCAGUUGUUUCUAGUUGUGUUCACUUUGUGCUUUCUCUGAAUGGGAAUAUCUUCUUUCAGCAAAGUUCUUCAUUGACCAGGAAACCAAAGAUUGCUUCUUUUCCAAGUUUGUUUUGUUUUUAAUCUUUUACCAAUGUGCAGUAUAUCUUAAGAAGGGAAGAGUGCUCUUGGGAGUAGAAGAACAUGCAAACAUUCUUUUUUCUUUAUUAUUAUUUGAGAUGGAGUCCCUCUCGGUCACCCAGGCUGGAGCGCAGUGGCAUGAUCUUGGCUUACUGCAACCUCCGCCUCCCAGGUUCAAGCAAUUCUCUUGCCUCAGCCUCCCAAGUAGCUGGGAUUACAGGCACACCACCAUUUCCAGCUUUUUUUUUUUUUUUUUUUUUGAUAUUUUUAGUAGAGAUGGGGUUUCACCAUGUUGGCCAGGCUGGUCUUGAACUCCUGACCUCAGGUGAUCUGCUUGCCUUGGCCUCCCAAAGUGCUGGGAUUACAGGCAUGAGCCACUUGCCUGGCCCCAAAAUUCUUAUACUGUAAAGCCUUGUAGUGGUCCUUAUUUUUUUUUUUUUGAGACGGAGUCUCGCUCUGUCACCCAGACUGGAGUGCAGUGGCACAAUCUCGGCUCACUGCAACCUCUGCCUCCCGAGUUCAAGCCCUUCUUCUGCCUCAGCCUCCCAAGUACCUGGGAUUACAGGCAUGCACCACCAUGCCCGGCUAAUUUUAUUUGUAUUUUUAGUAGAGACGGGGUUUCUCCAUGUUGGUCAGGCUGGCCUCGAACUCCUGACCUCAGGUGAUCCACCCGCCUCGGCCUCCUAGAGUGCUGGGAUUACAGGCGUGAGCCACCGAGCCCGGCCGGUCCUUAUUUUAUACAAGUGAUUAAGCCAAAAAUUUUCUUGAAUUUCUGAUACCAAAGAGCUUUAGGUAAAUAACUUCACACUCUAAUGCAAUGUAAUUCUUUCUUUGUGCUUUCAGAUUUCCUUACACUUCCUGUCCAGUUCUCUCUUCUAAAUCCAAUAUUACUCACUAGAUAAUUUCAGCCACUUAAAUAAAAAUAUCUAUUUUUAAGUCCUGGUUCAAGGGUUCCAAACUCACAUAAUUUCUCAACUUUUUGCCAGAAAGUUGAGCAUUUAUUCAUACUUAUUUUCAAUCCUAAGUGUUCUCCCAUGGGCAGCAGCACUUCUUGAGCUGUUUAGUACUGCCACACCUUUUUAUGUCUUUACUAUGUCAGCCUCUGAUCAUUUUCACUUUGAACUUCCUAAAGAUCACAAUUUCCUAUCCCUUCAAUCUGCGAUCCCUCUUCUUCCUUUCUUACUAGAUUAUGGUGUAGUUUGUACUAGACUGACUCAUUAAGACCUUGUACGCUUCCUGAGUCUGCUUAUUACUGGCUUUGUAAUCAAGGGUGAGUCUUUUUACUUCUCUAGGCUAGAUUUUCUCAUUUAUGAAAUGAGGACAUUUUUCUAGAUGCUGUAAAGCCCUUUCCAGCUGUAACAUUCUAUGAAUCUGUAAUUCCCUCGAGGAGCUAAGGAGGAUUAUGCUACUUUAAUAAAAAGCUGCUUUGGUGACAUUUGUUCGAGUAGAACAAGAGUGAUGCUGCUCAUUCUGACUUGAGCCAGAUGUAUUUCCUUUAUAGCAGGAGUAAUGGUCUAAGAAAUACUCAUUAGGAGAAAAAAAUUCUGCUUCUAAACAGUAUUAGUAAACAAAGAAUCUUGACUCAGUUGAAAAACCACCCAUUGCUCUCUAGAGCAGAAUGUCUGAAUGCUGGUUUUAUAGCACACUAGAAUAUCAGAAUGAGUUGACAGGUAUACCACAACUAAUUUGUAACUAGUUUGUGACUCACCUUUCUAAUGUAUUCGAAGUUAUCCCUAUAAUUAUAUUACUCUCGCUCAAAUUCUGAUAGAUUUCCUGAAUGGAAUAGGUGGAAUUAGGGCUAGGCUGCCAGAGACUGUGCCAAUGAGCAUCACCCGUCAUGUGUGAGAGAGCAGAAGAUAGCCUGUGAGCCAGUGCUCUAGAAAACAUCAUGUAGGAGGCCGGUCACGGUGGCUCACGCCUGUAAUCCCAGCACUUUGGGAGGCCGAGGUGGAUGGAUCAAGAGAUCGAGACCAUCCUGGCCAACAUGGUGAAAUUCCACCUCUACUAAAAAUACAAAAAUUAGCUGGGCGUGGUGGUGCGCGCCUGUAGUCCUAGCUGCUCGGGAGGCUAAGGCAGGAGAAUCACUUGAACCUGGGAGGCAGAGGUUGCAGUGAGCCGAGAUUGCACCACUGCACUCCAGCCUGGUGACAGAGUGAGACUCCGUCUCAAAAAAAAAAAAAAAAAAACCCGUGUAGGAGUACUGCCUCUCUGCUCUAGCAGUGGUCCUUCUACUGACAGUGCUGUCAGAGUCUGGUCUCCUAAAGAGCCAGGUCAUUUUCCAUUGUGUCAACUCAGAUGGUUGAGAUGUCCUUAGAUAUUCCUAGCUUGCCUAAAUAACUAGUCAGCAAUCUAUUUAAAUGUGAAGAGCCUAUCUCUGGUCUUUAAAUAAACACACACACACACACACACCCCUAGGAAAAGGAAUUCCUGAAACUUUUCAUUAUUGCAUAUGUUUCUGAUCAAGCAAUAUGUUAACCCUCUAAGUAGGAUUAGUGUCCCAUGAGUAUUUCUUCCAGCAGAAUCAUGUCUGCCUAAUGCUAAUCAGGAAUGUUGCAAACUGAAAUGCUCCUUUCCCCACUGCCCCCUAAUGACCACUUUCAGGAGGAAUACAUACAUUCUCUUGAUUUGUUUGUCCCCUUUCAGGCUGAUUCUCCACUUCCACCUGGAAGAAAAGACAGUAUUCCUUGAACUCCAUGACCUACUGGUACAGGAUCUACACUUAUGCCAUUGGCUUUCUGUCACUCCGCAACUUGUACUUUUUUUUUUGAGACAGGGUUUCACCCUGUCAGCCAGGCUGGAGUGCAAUGGUGUGAACGUGGCUCACUGUCGUCACUGCAGCCUUGAUAUCUCAAGCCCAAGUGAUCCUCCCACCUCAACCACCUGAGUAGCUGUGCCACCACACCCGGCUAAUUUUUGUAUUUUUUGUAGAGAUGGAGUUUCACCUUGUUGCCCAGGCUGAUCACAAACUCCUGGGCUCAAGCAAUCUCCCCACUUAGGCCUCCCAAAGUGCAGGGAUUAUAGGCAUGAGCCACCGCACCCCGCAGUACUUUCCCUCGUAUACAAGCUACUCUCCUGAAAAAAAUAGCAGGAACCCAUUCCAAUGUCCAAGCUCCCCUAAAGUGCCAACUCAGAAUAACUUUCAUGUUUAAAAACAGCUGUCUUCACAUUGCCCAUUGUGAGGUUGUAAAAGGAAGUUAAGAUGUCAAGCAAUUUAGAUUCUGUUACCCAUUUCCCUAUGAAAAGAGAUGUGUUAAAAGUCUUUAACUACUUAAAGGGUCAUCAUGAAAAAUAAGAAUUCUAUUCCAGAAGACAGAGUUAUACACAGGGAGGUGUAUUAUAUACUUGCUAAUAAAUUUUUGUGUAGGCUCUUUAGUAAAUUUAUCUGAUAAUGGAAUAAUCAGCCUUUUUGGUGGAAAGGUACAUACAGAAGCUAAAUCAUCAUCUGUUAAUAGUGUUUAAGAGAUUUCUUCAUUGAGAUGGAAUAUGGGCAAGAUGACCUUUAAGGUCUUUUUCACUUUUAUCAUUGGAAAUCCCCAGAAGCAAUCUGAUAGUCUUAAAACUUUGUCCUUUCUAAGUCCUUUGUAUUCAUUUUAGAGCUCUUCAGGAAACUAGAGAAUUUUGGACUUUGGUUGACAAAAGCGGUCUGACCUGUGUUCGUAGCUGGGAACAUGAAACACAAAAUUCUGGGUUUAAUCUUCUGAAGAAAUCUAUAAGUAGUUACUGGCAUAAAUGGUAUUACUAUACUAACAAAUUUAAAAGCCUAUAAUGUAUUAAAACUCUUUUUUACUCGAUUACUUUUAUUUUUUUAAGACACAGUCUCGCUUAUUGCCCCGGCUGGAGUGCAGUGGCACGGUCUCAGCUCACUGCAAUCUCCGCCUCCCAGGUUCAAGCGAUUCUCCUGCCUCAGCCUCCCAAGUAGCUGGAAUUAAUUACAGACGCCCACCACCAUGCCCGGCUAAUUUUUGUAUUUUUAGUAGAGAUGGGGUUUCACCGUGUUGCCUAGGCUGGUCUUGAACUCCUGACCUCAAGUGAUCAACCCACCUUGGCCUCCCAAAGUGCUGGGAUUACAGGCAUGAGCCACUGUGCCCAGCCCUCUUGAUAAUUUUUAUUCUUGUUUCUUCUUAUCUGUGGGACUCCAAUUAGAAUGGGGUUGAGAUUGUGGCAUUCAGUUUUAUACCAAUAUUUUACCCAAGUGUGUCAUGGCCUUUUUUAAUCAUUUUAAUAUCCCCAGAAAUGCUAGAAGUGUAAAGGAAUAACAGAGGUAAAUUUGCUGUCAUUUUAUGCCACAUCCUCUUUUCUUACUUUGCUUCUUGAUACAGAUUAUAGAGGUAAUUGUGAAGACAGUUGAACCUUAGAAGAUUGAGCUAAGAUUCUUUUUUUGGCAACCUGCAAGUAAUGUUUCAUUUUUCUAUUACGUGAUCUCUUUGCCCAUACAGUUGGCAGAUGUUUUUUCCCCCUUUUUCUACCUUAAACUUUUUUGUUUGGAGUACAGUCUAAACCAACAUCAGUUAGCCUUGAUUUUCUUUCUUUUUUGGACAAUUGUCUGGUUCAUUGACAAAAGUAACAAGUUUGGAACUAAGAGAUAUGUUACAAGCUGCACUUAACACCACCUGAAAACCCAAGAAUCAUCUGAAGGUUUUGUCAGUAGUAAGGUAGGUUUUGUGUGUGUGUGUGUGUGUGUGUGUGUGUGUGUGUGUGUGUGAAGAUGGAAUAGGGUGAAGGUGAAGAAACAGCUUGACUUGUGCCUGUUUUCAGAUAAAGGAGUAAAGUGAUCUACAAACUGUAACUAUCUUGAAAGAGAAAUUGAUCAUCAGAUGGUCGAGUACUCUUGGAAUGUCUCUUUGCUGUUUACUGUGGCCUCUUUACAAUGGUGAGACUUAUUUCUACCCUCUACUUUCCACUAUUAUUUUUUUCCCCUAUUGGAUAAUACUAGUCUGAGCAGCCCUAAUACUAGAUGUACCUAAACAGAGAUACAAGCCAAGUCAUUGUUCAGUGUAGUCAUUUCUUAGUAUCUGUUUAUAUUUUGUCACACAUCAGAAUGUAUAUUUUAUAGAGCAUGUGUUUGUCUACUUGUUUGUCUACUAUAAUAUGUCUUUAAUAAAGCUAAAAACAUUCUGA